UUCACUCUAGCCUGGGCAAUAGAGCAAGACUCUGUCUCAAAAAAAAAAGGUGAAUUUUAUUAAUCUUGUCCAAGAAAAAGCUCUUUCUUUCAUUGAUUUUCUCUAUUAUUUUUCUGUUUUGAUUUGACCUAUUUCUUCUCCUACCUUUAUUAUCUCCUUUCUUCCGCUUGCUCUGGAUUUAUUAUGCUUUCCUUUUACUACAGUCAAGUGGGAGUCUAGAGUCUUGAUUUGAAACCCUCCCUCUUUUUCUUUUUCUUUUUAAACAAUUAAUAGCAGUUUAUUUUAAAACAUUUUUGUGGGUACAUAGUAGGUGUAUAUAUUUGUGGGGUACAUGAAAUGUUUUGAUACAGGCAUGCAGUGUGAAAUCAUCACACUGUGGGAAAUGCUCCUCUUUUCUAAUGUAAACAUUUAGUGCUAUAAAUUUCCCUCCCAGCACUGCUUUAGCUAUGUGCCACAAAUUUUGAGAUGUAUUUUUGUUUUCACACGUCAGUGUAUUUUUUGAUUACCCUGGGGGCUUCCUCUUUGACCCAUGGAUUAUUUAGAACUGUGUGCCAUUUUGUUUUCAAGUAUAUGAAGCUGUCCUGUUAUCUUUCUGUUGUUGAUUCAUAGUUUGAUUCCGUUGUCGUCAGAGAACAUGCUUUGUAUGAUUUUAAUUCUUUAAAUUUGUUGAGGUUGAUUUUAUGGCCUGGAAUGUGGUCUAUCUUGAUGUAGCAGUCUGGGUCCAAUCAGGAAGUAGGAGCCAUACAAUAGGCUAAAUGAGAGAAGCUGAUGAUAAGAAUUACUAACUAUAAUGAAGAGGGACUAUAAGACAUAAGGGAACUCCAUGUGGCACCCUAGGAUUGAGAUUCAGCUUCUCAACUGAAAGAGACAGCUUCCAUUUCUCCCAGCAAGGACACACGUGGAAGGAGUCAGACCUCCCUGGAAGAGAUGUGAUUUGCCCACUGGAUAGCAGAGGAGUUGGCUGGCUUAGCAAGACUGAAGCUUAUCUGGAGUUGCUGGGCAAACAAUGGGCAACUUUCUGGAGUACAGGUGGGAGGUGGCAGGCAAUCUACAACCAGAGACGUGGGUGUGUUAUGGGAGUCUGGCACUAGUGGGACAGAAGUCUCCAGAGCUCCCAGAAAGACAGUGUGCCGGCUGUGUGGUUGCAGAAGGAGCAGAUCCAUGUGAACCCCCCAGCCACAGGCAGGCUGUGCAACAGCUUUGGUUUUUAUGUUGUGGGGGCUGCAGACAGAUUACUGCUGGGCUGAGGCUGCAAGGUUGCAGAGGGAGUGAGUCCUGGGGCCUGUGGCUGGGAGGGGGAACUCCAUGGCAUGUCCUCAUACCCACACCACUGGCCCUCUCGUGGGCCCCUCCUGGAAACUGCAGGAAGCCUCUUCCUCCUGCAAUGACCCUCCAACAUCCUCUGUUGGAAAAACUUAGCACUGUGUCCACUUUAAAGGAGAAAAUCUUUAAAAGUUUGCAUCCCUUAUCAUACAGCAUGUAUUGAAUGGCAUUUUUUGGAGCUGAGAGGCAAUAAAUUUCUAUCUGGCACAGUCUAUCCCUUUGCCUGUGCAGCCCCAUGUGUACCCUUUACAUGCAUGUGAACUUUCUUACAACAGAAUGGCUCUGUAUUUCCACCUAACAAGAUACAUCCAUGCUUCUAGCAAGUGAAGAGGUUCUCACUUGUUCGAAAUGAGCAGAUGCAGUCAUUGUACUCAGCACAGGCUGUAUCAAUUGCUCUUCAAAUUCAGUCAAGCUCUCACUGAAUAUUCUGUUCCCUAAAGCCUAAAUUGUAAAGUUAACUUCCAAUAACUCAUAUAUAAAAAUUUAAAACAUGAAGUAGGAGAAAGAAGUAGAGAAUGAUUAGUAAAGAUAAAAUAAAACUCAUUCAUAUAACACACAUAGAGACCAUACACAAACCCCCUCCAGUCCUCGUUUAUAUAAUUGAUCAUGAAGUUGUAGUUCAUAUCUGUGACUUUCUUCUUCCACCACCCAUUCCACAUCUUCCUUGACCUCAGCUGCCCUGGGUUCUUUACCUCUUGGAAUAUCUACUAACUCCUGAAAAGUAUGAGUAUGUACUUUUCUCCCAAAUUGCAGUUGUUCCACUAUGUGGCAACAGGUCCCUUUGAGAAGGCAUAAAGAAAGAUUUACAGUGUAUCCUUUUGGCAAUAGUAGAGUGUCCUUUUCAAGGGGACCUGGCUUUCCCUUCAAUCAAGGGCCUGUAGGUCUGCAAACUGCCUUAGUUCUGAAAACUGGGUAAAGGGCCGUGAGUCUCCAUUUGAUGACUGAGUCACGUUACUUGCCACCACACUUAGGACUUUUCCUAUGAUUUCCUAUGAUAUCAUAGUAGACUGACUGGUCUUUCCCUCCGAGGGACAACGUGAUCAGUUAGUUACUGCUAAGAUCUCUGCGAGCCAAAGAAUUCGGAUUCCUGCCAUUCCCUGUUGCUCCCGUGGCACGCUCACCUUCUCUUUGGCAAUGAAGUGAUGCCACUUGGUCCUCUGCUAUUCUGGGACCCCCCAACAACCACAGUGAAAUGAGGGAGCCUGUCUCAAUAGUGGUGUCCCCUACAGCUCUUCCUGGCCUGGAAAAAGAGCAACCACAGAUCUUUUCGGGGAUGCGGAUGCUCCCCUCAUUAAUGCAUUUCUCAGCGCCCUCCUGAAGAGGGGCCUUCUGGGUCUUCUUGAGGCAUGCCGCUGGGAGAGUUGGAGGUUGCCUGUGAUACACCCGGCCCAGCAGGCAUAUUUCCCAUAGUCUUUAGAGCCCCUCCUCUGUGUCAUGCCAGGGAAGCUCCAGCAUUCCGGCCUCACUAAAUGCAGGUCACCAUCAUUUCCAGAUUUCAGUCAACCAACCUAGGAAGCUGUUAAAGCCACAUCCAGCUGCACAACUAAUACACUAAAUUGAGACUCUCUGCAACAUCAGCCCUGUGGCUACAAAAAUGAGACAUUCUUUGAGGGCUGUCAUGGAGGCUGUGUGAUCCUCAGAUCAUGACUCAAGGUUUUCCAGCAUUGUGGGCCAUCCAGAUGAUGCGGAAUGGAGGUUCCAGAACCCACCUGCCCUGCCCCUCCUGCGAGGGACCAGCCAGCUCCCACUCCUGGCCCUCCAGGGGCCCCAGGUGGCCAGGCCUCACCUCACCUGACCCUGGGCCCUGUCCUUCUGCCGCCAGAGCAGGGCCUGGCCCCCCCCACUGUGUUCCUGAAGGCCCUGCCCAUCCCACUGUACCACACGGUGCCUCCCGGGGGCCUCCAGCCCCGCGCCCCGCUAGUGACGGGCAGCCUAGAUGGGGGCAACGUGCCCUUCAUACUCAGCCCUGUGCUGCAGCCUGAAGGGCCUGGCCCCACCCAGGUGGGGAAGCCGGCGGCCCCUACGCUGACGGUGAACAUCGUGGGCACUCUGCCUGUCCUGUCGCCGGGCCUGGGCCCCACGCUGGGCAGCCCAGGCAAGGUGCGGAAUGCGGGCAAGUACCUGUGUCCGCACUGUGGUCGCGACUGCCUGAAGCCCAGUGUUCUAGAGAAGCACAUCCGGUCCCACACGGGUGAGAGGCCCUUCCCGUGUGCCACCUGCGGCAUCGCCUUUAAGACCCAGAGCAAUCUCUACAAGCACAGGCGGACGCAGACGCACCUCAACAACUCCCGGCUGUCCUCAGAGUCCGAGGGCGCCGGGGGCGGCCUCCUGGAGGAAGGGGACAAGGCCGGAGAGCCCCCCAGACCAGAGGGCAGGGGCGAGAGCAGGUGCCAGGGGAUGCACGAAGGCGCCUCGGAGAGACCCCUUUCUCCGGGUGCCCACGUGCCCCUACUUGCCAAGAACCUGGAUGUGAGGACCGAAGCUGCUCCCUGUCCAGGGUCCGCAUUUGCCGACAGAGAGGCUCCUUGGGACUCUGCCCCCAUGGCGUCACCUGGGCUCCCAGCGGCCAGCACACAACCCUGGCGUAAGUUGCCAGAGCAGAAGUCGCCGACCGCCGGGAAGCCGUGCGCCCUGCAGCGGCAGCAGGCGACGGCAGCGGAGAAGCCCUGGGAUGCCAAGGCCCCCGAGGGCCGGCUGCGGAAGUGUGAGAGCACCGACUCGGGGUACCUGUCGCGCUCCGACAGCGCGGAGCAGCCGCAUGCGCCCUGCAGCCCCCUGCACAGCCUUUCGGAGCACAGCGCCGAGUCCGAGGGGGAGGGCGGCCCGGGCCCGGGGCCAGGGGUCGCAGGGGCCGAGCCCGGGGCGCGAGAAGCCGGCCUGGAGCUGGAGAAGAAGCGGCUGGAGGAGCGCAUCGCCCAGCUCAUCUCCCACAACCAGGCGGUGGUGGACGAUGCCCAGCUGGACAACGUGCGGCCCCGGAAGACCGGGCUGUCCAAACAGGGCAGCAUCGACCUGCCCACGCCCUACACCUACAAGGACUCCUUCCACUUUGACAUCCGCGCGCUGGAGCCAGGCCGUAGGAGGGCCCCGGGCCCCGUGCGCUCCACCUGGACGCCCCCAGACAAGUCUCGGCCCCUCUUCUUCCACUCCGUCCCCACUCAGCUCUCCACCACCGUGGAAUGUGUCCCCGUCACCAGGAGCAACUCGCUGCCCUUCGUCGAGGGCUCCAGGACGUGGCUGGAGCCCAGGGAGCCCCGGGACCCCUGGUCCAGGACGCAGAAGCCUCUGAGCCCCAGGCCCGGCCCAGCCCGCCUGGGCUGCCGCUCGGGACUAAGCUCGACUGACGUUCCCAGUGGGCAUCCCCGGGCCCUGGUCAGACAGGCCGCGGUGGAGGACCUGCCAGGCACCCCCAUUGGCGAUGCCCUGGUGCCCGCAGAGGACACAGACGCAAAGAGAACUGCUGCGCGGGAGGCCAUGGCCGGCAAGGGCAGAGCGGGCGGCAGGAAGUGCGGCCAGAGAAGGCUGAAGAUGUUCUCCCAGGAGAAGUGGCAGGUGUACGGGGAUGAGACGUUCAAAAGGAUCUACCAGAAAAUGAAAGCCAGUCCCCAUGGAGGCAAGAAAGCCAGGGAGGUGGGAAUGGGCAGUGGGGCAGAACUGGGCUUUCCUCUGCAGAAAGAGGCAGCAGGGAGCUCAGGCACAGUCCCCACCCAAGACAGGAGGACCCCUGUCCAUGAGGACAUAUCCGCAGGGGCAACGCCAGAGCCUUGGGGAAAUCCACCAGCCCUGGAGGCCUCCUUGGUGACUGAACCCACUAAGCAUGGGGAGACGGUGGCCAGGAGAGGAGACAGUGACCGACCCAGGGUGGAAGAGGCUGUGUCAUCCCCUGCACUGGGUGGCAGAGACAGUCCCUGUUCAGGCAGUAGGAGCCCCCUGGUCUCUCCAAAUGGGAGGCUGGAACUGGGGUGGCAGAUGCCCCCAGCACCUGGCCCCCUCAAAGGGGGUGAUGUAGAGGCUCCCAGGCCAGUUUGGCCGGACCCCAAGCUGGAAGGAGGUGCCCGAGGUGUGGGGGAUGUUCAGGAGACCUGCCUGUGGGCCCAGACUGUCCUGAGAUGGCCCAGCAGGGGCUCAGGGGAGGACAAGCUCCCCUCAGAGAGGAAGAAGCUGAAAGUGGAGGACCUGCACAGCUGGAAGCAACCAGAGCCUGUGAGCGCAGAGACCCCAGGUGGGCCCACGCAGCCUGCCUCUUUGUCAUCCCAGAAGCAGGAUGCCGAUCCCGGGGAGGUGCCAGGGGGCUCAAAGGAGAGUGCCAGGCAGGUGGGCGAGCCUCUGGAGUCCUCUGGAGCCUCCUUGGCUGCUGCUUCUGUUGCCCUGAAGAGGGUGGGGCCAAGGGACAAGGCUACCCCACUGCAUCCUGCAGCCCCAGCCCCCGCAGAGCACCCCUCGCUGGCCACCCCACCUCAGGCUCCUAGAGUGCUCUCUGCCCUGGCAGAUAAUGCCUUUUCCCCCAAGUACCUCCUCAGGUUACCUCAGGCAGAGACCCCCUUACCACUGCCCAUUCCCUGGGGACCAAGGCACAGCCAGGACUCUCUCUGCAGCAGUGGGUGGCCUGAAGAACGGGCAUCAUUUGUUGGGUCAGGACUGGGGACCCCUCUUUCUCCCAGCCCAGCCUCAGGCCCCUCCCCAGGUGAGGCGGACAGCAUCCUGGAGGACCCCAGCUGUUCCAGGCCACAGGAUGGGAGAAAAGGGGCACAGUUGGGGGGGGACAAGGGGGACAGGAUGGCCACUAGCAGGCCAGCAGCCAGGGAGUUGCCCAUCUCAGCACCAGGGGCUCCCAGGGAGGCUACCUCCUCCCCGCCCACUCCAACGUGUGAGGCACACUUAGUUCAGGACAUGGAGGGUGACAGCCACCGUAUCCAUCGCCUCUGCAUGGGCAGCACUUUGGCAAGGGCCAGGCUCUCUGGGGAUGUCCUGAAUCCCUGGGUACCCAACUGGGAGCUGGGGGAGCCUCCUGGGAAUGCCCCAGAAGAUCCUUCUUCAGGGCCCCUGGUGGGCCCCGACCCGUGUUCCCCCCUCCAGCCUGGCUCCUUCCUCACUGCCCUCACUCGGCCUCAGGGUGUGCCCCCAGGCUGGCCAGAGCUGGCCUUGUCUUCCCACUCAGGGACGUCCCGGAGCCACAGCACCCGCAGUCCCCACAGCACCCAAAACCCCUUUCCCUCACUGAAGGCUGAGCCGCGGCUCACGUGGUGUUGCCUGAGCCGCAGUGUCCCUCUGCCCGCGGAGCAGAAGGCAAAGGCGGCAUCUGUGUACUUGGCGGUGCACUUUCCUGGUAGCAGCCUCCGAGAUGAGGGUCCCAAUGGCCCUCCUGGGAGCAAUGGAGGAUGGACCUGGACAAGCCCUGGAGAAGGAGGGCCGGCGCAGAUGUCCAAGUUCUCCUACCCAACAGUCCCAGGGGUGAUGCCCCAGCACCAGGUGUCUGAGCCAGAAUGGAAGAAAGGCCUGCCUUGGAGGGCAAAGAUGUCUCGUGGGAACAGCAAGCAGAGAAAACUGAAGAUCAACCCUAAAAGGUACAAAGGGAAUUUCUUGCAGAGCUGUGUUCAGCUGAGAGCCAGUAGACUUCGCACACCAACCUGGGUGCGAAGAAGAAGCCGCCACCCUCCCGCACUUGAGGGACUGAAGCCAUGCAGGACCCCUGGGCAGACCUCUUCAGAAAUAGCAGGUCUGAAUCUGCAAGAGGAGCCAUCUUGUGCCACCUCAGAAUCACCUCCUUGUUGUGGGAAGGAAGAGAAGAAGGAAGGUGACUGCAGACAAACCUUAGGAACCCUCUCUCUUGGUACAAGUUCAAGAAUUGUCAGGGAAAUGGACAAACGAACUGUGAAGGAUAUUUCUCCAUCUGCUGGUGAGCAUGGUGACUGUACUACUCACAGCACUGCUGCCACAUCAGGAUUAUCUCUGCAAUCUGACACCUGCCUGGCAGUGGUUAAUGACGUGCCUCUACCCCCUGGCAAAGGUCUUGACCUUGGGUUGCUGGAGACUCAGCUGCUGGCCUCCCAGGAUUCAGUCUCAACAGAUCCCAAACCAUACAUCUUCUCAGAUGCUCAAAGGCCUUCUUCCUUUGGGUCCAAAGGAACUUUUCCCCACCAUGACAUUGCUACCUCUGUGGCUGCCGUUUGUAUUUCUCUGCCAGUGAGAACAGAUCACAUAGCCCAGGAAAUUCACAGUGCUGAAUCACGAGACCACAGCCAGACUGCAGGGAGGACUCUGACAUCAAGCUCCCCAGACAGCAAAGUCACAGAAGAGGGCAGAGCACAGACCCUCUUGCCAGGGAGACCUUCAUCUGGACAAAGAAUUUCAGAUUCGGUUCCACUGGAGUCAACUGAAAAAACUCAUCUUGAAAUACCAGCUUCAGGACCAAGUUCAGCUAGUUCACACCACAAGGAAGGGAGACACAAGACGUUUUUUCCUUCCAGAGGCCAGUAUGGGUGUGGGGAAAUGACUGUCCCCUGCCCCUCUUUAGGAAGUGACGGUAGGAAACGUCAGGUAUCUGGAUUAAUCACUCGGAAAGAUUCUGUGGUUCCUUCUAAGCCAGAGCAGCCCAUAGAAAUUCCUGAAGCCCCUUCUAAAUCCCUCAAGAAGAGGAGUCUGGAAGGAAUGAGAAAGCAAACUCGAGUAGAGUUCAGUGACACCAGCAGCGACGAUGAAGACCGAUUAGUUAUAGAAAUAUGAAGCUUCCAGAGAAACAUGGUGUCUGGUCAAAAAGACUGUUGACGCUUCACAAGUAAAUGUUGUCAGGCUGGCGGAAGAACUAAACUCUAUCUGUGAAACACCUACAGAUUAGGAAAGCCAUUUUGAGUUAUUUACAAGCCAACUCCAACCAACUUCUGACCCCCAACUCAGCCGCAGCGUUCCCCAGCUCCCCUUGGGAGUGCUCUGCUCAUCUUCAAAUGGUGCCAGGCAGGGCAGACAUGGCAAGGAAGCAAACUCUGCAAAUGGUCAACGUGCACAGUGACUGGGCCUUGACUCCCAGCCUCGUCUUCUGCACCUGUCCCCCACUGCCUCUCUGCAAUCAAAUGGCACUAACCAAGAAAGCCACCAUCAACACAUUUCUCCACAAGUGGACCCCACACAGUCGAGGCAACUGGCUUUCUCCAUUAGUAAACUGAGGAUUUGCUUCCAAGGUGGAGAGCACACUUGGGAUAAUUGGAGUAGCUUGACAAAGAGACGGGGGUGUGAACUGGGCACAAAGAUACUUCUGUUCAUUUUGGAGACAAAAUUCAGAUACAUUAAAAAACUGAAGCUUGUUCAGAGUAAUUCACGUCCUUGGUGGAGUUGUAAAUACACUUCAAAAUGCCUAUGAUCCGGUGACAUGCUGAUUACUUUUAAAUGUUGCACAAAUGGUCAAUGCUUAUUUAUGGUCAGAUGAUGCAAGCACAUGCUCUUGUGCCUGGUGCGUUUGCUGUGGAGAUCUCUGAGACUGUCGGUUUUUCUAGUUCUUGCAAAGGAACGGUGUUAAAAGUUAAUAGAACUGUCUCUCUGUAAUGAGUCAUUUUUUGAGAGGGAAAAAUUCACUUAUUUUCCUCUGAUUCUUCUUGUCAUAUUGUGCUCUGAGCAAUUUCAAUUAGAGGGUUACAUUUUAGUAAUCUGUACAGCUUCAACUGAUGCCUGCUCGUCGUGACGGGAGCCUUUUAGAUUUCCUUCAGAAGCUUCAAGGAUACAAAACUAAUUGGAGUUUUGACGCUGUUUUACAUCUCGGUAAUUUUAUUUUCGGGGCUUAGUGUUACUUUGCUGUCAAAUUAAAUCAGCCUCUGUAUUGUGCACGUCAGAACUGCACAGAGAAAAUUCCCCAGUAUUCCAAGCCGGUGCGCCCCUGUGCAGAAGAAAACAGAUCUACGUCAGCCAGCCCGGGGGGCAAAGCCUCAGUUCCACUGCCUUCCUCUCCCUCUCCUUCCACGGGAGAGGAGAAACUUAAAGAGGUUUACAUUGCUGCAUUUCAAUAAAAUUUUAUACUUGCUUUUGGUAUGAUUUUGUACAAUUUGAAAUUUGUAGCUGAGCUCUUUUGGUGUAACUUUGAUGUAAUGAUGUUCAUAUGACAUCUUGUACUUCAGAGACACAGCAGCAAUGCAGAGCAUCUCACACAUGUGAAUACACUUCAGUCAGUCUGUGCCUGUGACUAAGUAUGGUCAAAUUUCAAGUAUCUUCAUGUGAAUUUUCCAAUUUUGGUGUUUUUCAUAGAAAACUUCAAUGCCAGACCAGCUUCCCUGGUUACUUAGCAUAUAUUUGUGACCAUUUCAUAUGCACUCAUAAAUAUCCAAGGAUUUCAGGCCCAGCCAAGAAAAACAUAAGAAGGGAGGUAAAAAGGAUGUUGGACAUUGACUUAGUGUACUUUUUAAACCCAACAAAAGCGAUGUGGUGAUUAUCUCCCUUUUCGAAGGAUUCAUGCCACUGUAAUGAGAGAGGCAGUGUAGGCAAAUGGUCUGAGCCUUGGAUGGAGAUUGAAGUCCUGACUUUAGCUGGGAAAUCUUGGUUAAGAGUCUUUCUGUACCUUAGUUUCCCUAAGUGAGAAUAAGAGAGUUGGACAAGACGAAUGUAUCUCCAGGUUCCAAUUUUUCUGAGAAUGGUUGAUAGAGAAGCUGCUCUCUCCUUAAAAUGCAUGGACUCAAUGGCUUGAAGAUAUUCCCCAUGGGGAACCAUUGCCACGGAGGCCUUGCAUGCAAGAAGUUUGGGUGGGGACAGUGAGGAACUGAAACACAAGCACCUUCCACCAAUUAUUGCUGUGAAGAACCUGAGCCUGAAGAAGCUCCAUCUAAUUUUUUCCCCAGAGUUCCAGAUUUUAGGGUGCAAUCAUCCAGCCUAUACAUGUGGCUCAUAGUUCAAAAAAUUAAAAGCAAAACCAGAACUCUCCAGUAGGAAUGGAGAAAACCUAUCUGUAGGCUGAACUGGCUCCUUUGUCUUAGGAGGCACUGGUCAGGGGAAAAAAGCUGUCUUCCAGACCCCUCCUUUCUGGGUGGCUACUGUGGAAUCAACGGGGUCACUGGCUGUAAAUCAGUAAGUCAUAGCUCCAAACAGCACCAACUUCAGGAUGAUGGUGGAAGCUCUGUCCCUAUAGGAGCCACCGUUGCCAGCUGUCACAUCCCAACCUAGGUCAAAUAUGGCGGAAUAUUGAUUUCGUCUCUAACUCCCUGUAUCUCUUACAAAGGUAAAGCAGGUAGCGAAGCCACCUUGCUUCCCUGGUCUUUGCCUAGUGGCUGGCAAUGUUUACAAGUGUACCUUACUUUAUAUCAACAUGAAUUUGUGAAAAAGCUGUAUGUCAAUGGAUUUUUUAAAAAUUAAAAAUGUAUUUUGAAUGACCCUAAGGGAGCUGGCUCUUUAAAAGCAUCCUAAGGUAAAGAUUUUUUUUAAAUGAAGAAUCUUUUUAUAAAGCAAUGAACAAUCUCUGAUUUUAUAAAUCUUAAUUUUCCUAUGGGUUUUCUUAAAGUGAAAUACAAUUAUAAGAAUACAUUUUAAGGGUAACAUUAACAACCUAGAACCCAGUUUGGGUUACUAAAAAUAAAAUGUCAGUAUUAUCAAUUGAUAACUACCACAGUUUUAUACUCUGCAAGUGUGUACUGCAUGAUGGUUAAGGAAAAACAAAUUUAUUUUAGAACAAAGCAAACCAGAGUUUAAAGAUCAGGGAUUUCCUUCUUUCCCCAGUGCUAAUUUUCCCAGUGUUAAUUUUAUUAUAUCUUUAGGUAAGGGUCUUAACCAACUGAUGCCUCAGUUUCUUCCACAGAGAAUAGUUAGAGGGAUGCUGUCAUGAACUAAGGGAAGGGCACUGAAUUUUUUUUUGCCAAUAUCAAAAGUGACAUUUCCCCAUGAUGUUCAAGACUCACCAGGUUUCUCUCUCCACCUGUACCUACACCCAGCUAGAUCUUGUCGUUAAAGAUGUAUGGAGGGAAGAGGUUUCAAUCCUUCCCUCCUUGGCAACCUACAUUGUUAAGUGACUCAAAGUCAUGUGAUUUUUGGUGGACAACUGGAAUCCUCCUUCUUGUAAAACACAUUGAAAAACAGCUCAUCUCUCCUGUUAGGCUUAACCCUUGAGAUUUGAGACAAAGCUAAUAAUCCCCUUUGGUUCACAUCUCACAGUAACCAGGAGAACCUAUGGUUCAUUUGCCAAGUGAUUAAAAAAAAAGAUGGAGGAGGGUGUCUCUGAAUUUUAAUGGAAACACUGCCAAUAGCAUGGUGGGUAACCUAGGGCAAGACAGACUUUUUCUUCCUGAAAUCACUCUUCUAAAGCUGAGACCGGAAGAGGAACCUUGCAGAAGUGCACUGUGACCACAGUUCUUGGCAUGAAAGAUAAACAAUUUGCAGUCUCAUGCCAAAAAGUAUUUCCUUGCAUUUACAUUCAUUACUUAGAAUGAUCACAUUAUUCAUUUUUUUCCCCAGCACAGAAAUUUGCAUUUUGCACAGAAUUUGCCUGGUGCAGCAGAUCUUUAUAGUUAUGGAAACUGUCAUCAUUAUCGGAAUGUGCUGCUGCUCAACUCCCCAGACAUAAUUUAAUAUGGUGAGGAGAAUAUGACCUGCCUGGCUCUAUGGGUGAUCAUAUUUCUACUGCUGCAGCAAGCUGGGCUUGUGUAUUUUUCCUCACUUCAGUUGUUCUUCCCAUAGUUCAUGUAGGGAGGCACUUUGGCUUUUGAAACACUACAUUUCUCAAUAUUUAAGCACAAUUUAUUGUCCUUAUUUUUCAGAACCCAUUAAAUAUAAGGGUCAGAACCUAGAAAAUCUUAUGUGCUGGAUUUCUACCCUGUAUGAUUCUUUUCAUCCAUGCUUUGCACUUACGUAGGAAUAUACAUAAUUUGGUCUGAAGAAGUAUAGGAACAGUUGAGCACAUUACUUCACCACUGGAAGAAUAGGAACCAGGGAAAAACAUCAGCCUCUGCCACUUGGAGCACUAGAGGAUGACGGAAUGUCUUGUAUAUGCGGUCAACUGUUCAGGAUUUACUACUCAAUUGGUUGUUCACAAUCAGGGAAAUGAUUGGCUUCUUGGUUGUUUGUUGAACUUUCUUUCUUUAUAUGGUUAAAUUAUUUUGUUUUGAUAAAAAUAAAACUUAAAAUGCAAA